AGUCAGGUGGGUGCCAGGCCCUGGCCGUGGCGAAAGAGCCGGCGGAGCCGGAGACCCGCUCCCGGAGACGCCGCCUCGCGAUCCCCGCGCGGGCGGGACCGGGCGGCCGGCAUCAUGACCCUGUUUCACUUCGGGAACUGCUUCGCUCUUGCCUACUUCCCCUACUUCAUCACCUACAAGUGCAGCGGCCUGUGAGUGCGGGAAGGGCGCGGGGCGGAGAGGGCGCGGGGCCCGGGCCGACCCUCACCUCCCGCUUCUCCAGGUCCGAGUACAACGCCUUCUGGAAAUGCGUCCAGGCUGGAGUCACCUACCUCUUUGUCCAACUCUGCAAGAUGCUGUUCUUGGCCACUUUCUUUCCCACCUGGGAAGGCGGCAUCUAUGACUUCAUUGGGGAGUUCAUGAAGGCCAGCGUGGAUGUGGCAGACCUGAUAGGUCUAAACCUUGUCAUGUCCCGGAAUGCCGGCAAGGGAGAGUACAAGAUCAUGGUUGCUGCCCUGGGCUGGGCCACUGCUGAGCUUAUUAUGUCCCGCUGCAUUCCCCUAUGGGUCGGAGCCCGGGGCAUUGAGUUUGACUGGAAGUACAUCCAGAUGAGCAUAGACUCCAACAUCAGUCUGGUCCAUUACAUCGUCGCGUCUGCUCAGGUCUGGAUGAUAACACGCUAUGAUCUGUACCACACCUUCCGGCCAGCUGUCCUCCUGCUGAUGUUCCUCAGUGUCUACAAGGCCUUUGUUAUGGAGACCUUCGUCCACCUCUGCUCGCUGGGCAGUUGGGCAGCUCUACUGGCCCGAGCAGUGGUAACGGGGCUGCUGGCCCUCAGCACUUUGGCCCUGUAUGUCGCCGUUGUCAAUGUGCACUCCUAGGCUUGGUGUCUCAGACAUUGAUGUACCUUUUCCCUGCCUCACUCCAGGUUUUAGUGAAGUAAACAGUAUUUGGAAAGUU